GCCGGAGAGCGCGGGCGGCUGGGGAAUGGCUGCUGCCAUGGUGCCGGGGCGCAGCGAGAGCUGGGAGCGCGGGGAGCCUGGCCGCCCGGCCCUGUACUUCUGCGGGAGCAUUCGCGGCGGACGCGAGGACAGGACGCUGUACGAGCGGAUCGUGUCUCGGCUGCGGCGAUUCGGGACAGUGCUCACCGAGCACGUGGCGGCCGCCGAGCUGGGCGCGCGCGGGGAAGAGGCUGCUGGGGGUGACAGGCUCAUCCAUGAGCAGGACCUGGAGUGGCUGCAGCAGGCGGACGUGGUCGUGGCAGAAGUGACACAGCCAUCCUUGGGUGUAGGCUAUGAGCUGGGCCGGGCCGUGGCCUUUAACAAGCGGAUCCUGUGCCUGUUCCGCCCGCAGUCUGGCCGCGGUGAGCACCCCAAGCCUCCCUCCUGGCUUUCUAUGGACCCAGCCCUCAGCUCCUUCCCUGGUGGGCUCUGAGCACCGCGCCUCUCCCAAGGGGUAAGGGAGCUGUGAGGGUGUGGAUGGGAGGCAGCUUCACCUUUCCCUGCCCUUUCCAGUGCUUUCGGCCAUGAUCCGGGGAGCAGCAGAUGGCUCUCGGUUCCAGGUGUGGGACUAUGAGGAGGGAGAGGUGGAGGCCCUGCUGGAUCGAUACUUCGAGGCUGAUCCUCCAGGGCAGGUGGCUGCCUCCCCUGACCCAACCACUUGACUUAAUCUCACUUUCUUAAAUUCUUCUAUUCUCAGACACUGCUCUAGUACCAUUCCUUCCUCUUAGCCCCAGGAGCAAAUUAAAAGGUACAGUUAAAAUCCUAA